GUUGUCGGUAGCCGCCCCGGGAACAAGGACCGGAGCUGGAUCCGCGGUGCGGCUGUGGCUCUUUAGGGUGAGAUCUGCUGUACCAGUCUCACAGGAGUCAGCAUUGGUAAUAGUGCUGUGCUGCGGAAGAGUGGAGUCUAAACUUUUUCAUUGCCAGUGCCCCGAAACUGGAGUGUGAAGGACCGAGACAAAAUGAAGACUGUGCUCAUGGUUGCUGAAAAGCCGUCCUUGGCACAGUCAAUUGCCAAAAUCCUCUCUAGAGGGAGCCUGUCCUCACACAAAGGGCUGAACGGGGCCUGCUCAGUCCACGAGUACACUGGGACCUUUGCUGGCCAGCCAGUGCGCUUCAAGAUGACGUCUGUCUGUGGUCACGUGAUGACCCUGGAUUUCCUGGGAAAAUACAACAAAUGGGACAAAGUGGACCCCGCAGAACUGUUCAGCCAAGCUCCCACGGAGAAGAAAGAAGCUAACCCCAAGCUGAACAUGGUGAAGUUCCUGCAGGUGGAGGGCAGAGGCUGCGACUACAUCGUGCUGUGGCUGGACUGCGACAAGGAGGGGGAGAACAUCUGCUUUGAGAAAUGAAGCCACUUAUUCCCAGUAAGGAAGCUGCGUGGCCAGGCUCCGGCGGCGACCCUAGUCCCACUGCACGGCCUUCCUAGUUCUUGAUGCUGUUCUGCCCGUCAUGAACAAGGCCCAUGGUGGCGAGAAGACCGUGUUCCGGGCCAGGUUUAGCUCCAUCACGGACACAGACAUCUGUAAUGCCAUGGCCUGCCUAGGCGAGCCUGACCACAACGAGGCGCUCUCAGUGGAUGCUCGCCAGGAGCUGGACCUGCGAAUCGGCUGUGCAUUCACCAGGUUUCAGACUAAAUAUUUCCAGGGGAAAUACGGUGAUUUAGACAGCUCUCUCAUCUCCUUUGGGCCGUGUCAGACUCCAACCCUGGGAUUCUGUGUGGAGAGACAUGAUAAAAUCCAGUCCUUCAAACCAGAGACCUACUGGGUGCUGCAGGCCAAGGUUAACACUGACAAAGACAGAUCUCUCCUUUUGGACUGGGACCGAGUAAGAGUGUUUGACCGGGAGAUCGCACAGAUGUUUUUAAACAUGACAAAGCUGGAGAAGGAAGCCCAGGUGGAGGCCACAAGCAGGAAAGAAAAGGCCAAGCAGAGGCCCCUGGCCCUGAACACUGUGGAGAUGCUGCGUGUGGCCAGCUCUUCUCUGGGCAUGGGGCCGCAGCACGCCAUGCAGACGGCUGAGCGGCUCUACACGCAAGGCUACAUCAGCUACCCACGGACAGAGACCACCCACUACCCUGAGAACUUUGACCUGAAGGGCUCUCUGCGGCAGCAGGCCAACCACCCCUACUGGGCCGACACGGUGAAGCGGUUGUUAGCAGAAGGUAUCAACCGCCCGCGGAAAGGCCAUGACGCCGGCGACCAUCCCCCCAUCACCCCCAUGAAGUCUGCCACAGAGGCCGAAUUAGGGGGUGACGCGUGGCGGCUCUAUGAGUACAUCACCAGACACUUCAUCGCCACGGUCAGCCAUGACUGCAAGUACCUGCAGAGCACCAUCUCCUUCAGAAUUGGGCCCGAGCUCUUCACCUGCUCCGGGAAGACCGUCCUCUCACCAGGCUUCACGGAGGUCAUGCCCUGGCAGAGCGUGCCCCUGGAGGAGAGCCUGCCCACUUGCCAGCGGGGUGAUGCCUUCCCUGUGGGCGAGGUGAAGAUGCUGGAGAAGCAGACGAACCCACCCGACUACCUGACGGAGGCCGAGCUCAUCACGCUCAUGGAGAAGCAUGGCAUCGGCACGGAUGCCAGCAUCCCUGUGCAUAUCAACAACAUCUGCCAGCGCAACUAUGUCACGGUGGAGAGCGGGCGCCGGCUCAAGCCCACCAACCUCGGCAUCGUCCUGGUGCACGGCUACUAUAAGAUUGAUGCAGAGCUGGUGCUCCCCACCAUCCGCAGUGCAGUGGAGAAGCAGCUGAACCUGAUCGCCCAGGGCAAGGCCGACUACCGCCAGGUCCUGGGCCACACCCUGGACGUGUUCAAGAGGAAGUUCCACUACUUUGUCGACUCCAUUGCUGGCAUGGAUGAGUUGAUGGAGGUGUCUUUCUCGCCCCUGGCGGCCACAGGCAAGCCCCUCUCACGCUGUGGGAAGUGCCACCGCUUCAUGAAGUACAUCCAGGCCAAGCCAAGCCGCCUGCACUGCUCCCACUGCGAUGAGACCUACACGCUCCCCCAGAACGGCACCAUCAAGCUCUACAAGGAGCUCCGCUGCCCUCUGGAUGACUUCGAGCUGGUCCUGUGGUCAUCAGGCUCUCGGGGCAAGAGCUACCCGCUGUGCCCCUACUGCUACAACCACCCACCCUUCCGAGACAUGAAGAAAGGUGAGUGCAGCCACUCCCUCCUGUCCACAGGUAGCUGCAGUCUCUUUUCAGUGCCAACCCCUGCCUUGCACCAGGCUGGACUCUGAGGGGACCCCUCACCCUGGCCUUUCCUGCACUCAUUGGCACUGAGACGAGAGACCCUGGAUGUAGCUGGGGCACUGCUUAGGCCUCAGCCAGUGGUGCCACCCUCUCUCUGUGUCAGAAUCGAGCAGGCAACCCUAGUCCACCCUCAGGACCUGGGCACAGGUGUGCAGUGCUCCCUCUGGAGCUGAGUGAGCAAGAGGAUGCAGCAGUCGGGGGACCCACCCGGUGAGCGGGCACCCCCAGUCAGCGUCCACCACCGUCCUCCAUCCUCAUCCUCGUCCUCAUUACUGGAGGAGGGAGCGCAUGUCCAGGCAGGCAGGACAGAGCACCGAGCCAGACCAGGAAUCAGCGGGAGUGAGGCAUCUGCCCACAUUCACCGUGUGCUCUGCAGAAAGCUCCCUCAGGCCUCAGUCUGCACCCAGGCUGCCCCGGGAGUGAGACCCCAUCCCUGCCCUCCUGCUGCCGCCAGAGUAGCUGACAGGGUGGUUCCAUGUGGCCCAGUGACAUGAGGGUCAUGUGGCAUUACCAGUAACAAGCUGGCAGCAAAGCAAAGGGGGGAUGGAGUCAGCUGAAACCCACUGGGAUGGUGCCAGCGAGGGGCCUUGAAAGUUGAGGAGGUUUCAGGUAAGCAGAAAACAGGGGUAAUGGCAGCCAGGAGCCGAAACAUGAGCAAGGCUGUCCCCAAGAGCAAGGCCAAGAAGAGUUCCUUCUGCUGGGACGAGGGAUCCAGGAGCUUGAGGCAUUGGGAGCAGGCAGCAGAGGGCAGGUGGGCACAGUGGGCGUGCCUUUACAGGGCUCCCUUCUCCCGCCAGGCAUGGGCUGCAACGAGUGUACGCACCCCUCCUGCCAGCACUCGCUGAGCAUGCUGGGCAUCGGCCAGUGCGUGGAAUGUGAGAGCGGGGUGCUGGUGCUGGACCCCACCUCGGGCCCCAAGUGGAAGGUGGCCUGCAACAAGUGCAACGUGGUAGCGCACUGCUUCGAGAACGCCCACCGCGUGCGGGUGUCCGCCGACACCUGCAGUGUCUGUGAGGCCGCCUUGCUUGAUGUGGACUUCAACAAGGCCAAGUCCCCACUCCCGGGCGAUGAGACGCAGCACAUGGGCUGCGUCUUUUGUGACCCCGUCUUCCAGGAGCUGGUGGAGCUGAAGCAUGCGGCCUCCUGCCACCCCAUGCACCGCGGUGGACCAGGGAGAAGGCAGGGUCGAGGGCGGGGCCGGGCCAGGAGGCCCCCUGGGAAGCCCAACCCCAGACGGCCCAAGGACAAGAUGUCAGCCCUGGCCGCCUACUUUGUAUGAUGACCCUGUCCUCCCUCACCCAGGCUGCAGUGCCAUGCAGACACCUCAUGGCACUUCAAACUAUUAAAAUGCAUUUUAUCUUAUCCAGA